CUCUCAACAUAAGACAGUGACCAGUCUGGUGACUCACAGCCGGCACAGCCAUGAACUACCCGCUAACGCUGGAAAUGGACCUCGAGAACCUGGAGGACCUGUUCUGGGAACUGGACAGAUUGGACAACUAUAACGACACCUCCCUGGUGGAAAAUCAUCUCUGCCCUGCCACAGAGGGGCCCCUCAUGGCCUCCUUCAAGGCCGUGUUCGUGCCCGUGGCCUACAGCCUCAUCUUCCUCCUGGGCGUGAUCGGCAACGUCCUGGUGCUGGUGAUCCUGGAGCGGCACCGGCAGACACGCAGUUCCACGGAGACCUUCCUGUUCCACCUGGCCGUGGCCGACCUCCUGCUGGUCUUCAUCUUGCCCUUUGCCGUGGCCGAGGGCUCUGUGGGCUGGGUCCUGGGGACCUUCCUCUGCAAAACUGUGAUUGCCCUGCACAAAGUCAACUUCUACUGCAGCAGCCUGCUCCUGGCCUGCAUCGCCGUGGACCGCUACCUGGCCAUUGUCCACGCCGUCCAUGCCUACCGCCACCGCCGCCUCCUCUCCAUCCACAUCACCUGUGGGACCAUCUGGCUGGUGGGCUUCCUCCUUGCCUUGCCAGAGAUUCUCUUCGCCAAAGUCAGCCAAGGCCAUCACAACAACUCCCUGCCACGUUGCACCUUCUCCCAAGAGAACCAAGCAGAAACGCAUGCCUGGUUCACCUCCCGAUUCCUCUACCAUGUGGCGGGAUUCCUGCUGCCCAUGCUGGUGAUGGGCUGGUGCUACGUGGGGGUAGUGCACAGGUUGCGCCAGGCCCAGCGGCGCCCUCAGCGGCAGAAGGCAGUCAGGGUGGCCAUCCUGGUGACAAGCAUCUUCUUCCUCUGCUGGUCACCCUACCACAUCGUCAUCUUCCUGGACACCCUGGCGAGGCUGAAGGCCGUGGACAAUACCUGCAAGCUGAAUGGCUCUCUCCCCGUGGCCAUCACCAUGUGUGAGUUCCUGGGCCUGGCCCACUGCUGCCUCAACCCCAUGCUCUACACUUUCGCCGGCGUGAAGUUCCGCAGUGACCUGUCGCGGCUCCUGACGAAGCUGGGCUGUACCGGCCCUGCCUCCCUGUGCCAGCUCUUCCCUAGCUGGCGCAGGAGCAGUCUCUCUGAGUCAGAGAAUGCCACCUCUCUCACCACGUUCUAGGUCCCAGUGUCCCCUUUUAUUGCUGCUUUUCCUUGGGGCAGGCAGUGAUGCUGGAUGCUCCUUCCAACAGGAGCUGGGAUCCUAAGGGCUCACCGUGGCUAAGAGUGUCCUAGGAGUAUCCUCAUUUGGGGUAGCUAGAGGAACCAACCCCCAUUUCUAGAACAUCCCUGCCAGCUCUUCUGCCGGCCCUGGGGCUAGGCUGGAGCCCAGGGAGCGGAAAGCAGCUCAAAGGCACAGUGAAGGCUGUCCUUACCCAUCUGCACCCCCCUGGGCUGAGAGAACCUCACGCACCUCCCAUCCUAAUCAUCCAAUGCUCAAGAAACAACUUCUACUUCUGCCCUUGCCAACGGAGAGCGCCUGCCCCUCCCAGAACACACUCCAUCAGCUUAGGGGCUGCUGACCUCCACAGCUUCCCCUCUCUCCUCCUGCCCACCUGUCAAACAAAGCCAGAAGCUGAGCACCAGGGGAUGAGUGGAGGUUAAGGCUGAGGAAAGGCCAGCUGGCAGCAGAGUGUGGCCUUCGGACAACUCAGUCCCUAAAAACACAGACAUUCUGCCAGGCCCCCAAGCCUGCAGUCAUCUUGACCAAGCAGGAAGCUCAGACUGGUUGAGUUCAGGUAGCUGCCCCUGGCUCUGACCGAAACAGCGCUGGGUCCACCCCAUGUCACCGGAUCCUGGGUGGUCUGCAGGCAGGGCUGACUCUAGGUGCCCUUGGAGGCCAGCCAGUGACCUGAGGAAGCGUGAAGGCCGAGAAGCAAGAAAGAAACCCGACAGAGGGAAGAAAAGAGCUUUCUUCCCGAACCCCAAGGAGGGAGAUGGAUCAAUCAAACCCGGCGGUCCCCUCCGCCAGGCGAGAUGGGGUGGGGUGGAGAACUCCUAGGGUGGCUGGGUCCAGGGGAUGGGAGGUUGUGGGCAUUGAUGGGGAAGGAGGCUGGCUUGUCCCCUCCUCACUCCCUUCCCAUAAGCUAUAGACCCGAGGAAACUCAGAGUCGGAACGGAGAAAGGUGGACUGGAAGGGGCCCGUGGGAGUCAUCUCAACCAUCCCCUCCGUGGCAUCACCUUAGGCAGGGAAGUGUAAGAAACACACUGAGGCAGGGAAGUCCCCAGGCCCCAGGAAGCCGUGCCCUGCCCCCGUGAGGAUGUCACUCAGAUGGAACCGCAGGAAGCUGCUCCGUGCUUGUUUGCUCACCUGGGGUGUGGGAGGCCCGUCCGGCAGUUCUGGGUGCUCCCUACCACCUCCCCAGCCUUUGAUCAGGUGGGGAGUCAGGGACCCCUGCCCUUGUCCCACUCAAGCCAAGCAGCCAAGCUCCUUGGGAGGCCCCACUGGGGAAAUAACAGCUGUGGCUCACGUGAGAGUGUCUUCACGGCAGGACAACGAGGAAGCCCUAAGACGUCCCUUUUUUCUCUGAGUAUCUCCUCGCAAGCUGGGUAAUCGAUGGGGGAGUCUGAAGCAGAUGCAAAGAGGCAAGAGGCUGGAUUUUGAAUUUUCUUUUUAAUAAAAAGGCACCUAUAAAACAGGUCAAUACAGUACAGGCAGCACAGAGACCCCCGGAACAAGCCUAAAAAUUGUUUCAAAAUAAAAACCAAGAAGAUGUCUUCACAUAUUGUAUUUAUAUAUUUAUAUUUAUAUAUAUAUUUAUAUAAUGGUACAAAAUGGCUGGGGGUGUGGCCAUGGAUGGAGGGAAGAGUAGGCUGGCCUGUGGCGUGGGUGGGAGGAGAGGGGACGGAGAGGGCACUCGGCCCGCUGCAAUCUGACCCCUCUCUCCUCAGGGCAGGAAACACAGAGUCAGACAGUUUGGGGGGGUCUUGGGCCAGGGGUGGAGGGCUCAAGGGCACAGGGCCCAGGCUGAGGCAGGGCGGGCAAAGCGCCUGGCAGGAUGAAGGGCAAGUGGCCCCCCAAACACAGAGGCCCUGGCCAUGGACCCUGGGAGGUGACCGGGGUGAGUCAGGGGCCUGUUGUCAGCCCCAGAGGAAGCGCUGGACCUGGCCGAUGGUGGGCCGAGAGGACAGCACCAGGCUGGGAGAAGUGGGGCGAGUUCCCUUUGUAUUACAGCUGCCAGUGCAAGACCAGGCCCUCCAGGCCAGGAAGGCUAGGGACGGGUCCUGGUAGAAGACACCCUGUCUAGAAUGGCCCUUGGUCCUGGAGGUGGGGCGCAAAAGGCCUCAGCCAGGGAACUGCCCUGCCACCUCCCGAGGCAGGAAAGGAAGUGAGAAAAGGAGAAGUUUUUUUACUCCUGGGGCCAAAGUAGGGGGACAAACACCCAGUCGUAUAUGGCUUCAGCUCUGACCAAAGGCGGAUAGGGAGCUCUCCUGGGUAGGAGCAGGGAGCCAAGGGGGAGGCAGUGGCUGUGCCUGGGUGGGCACAGACAGAUCUGGUACAUGGCCCUGAGCCCUGGGCAGAGGGACAACCUUGCCGGUGAGUGGGCAGGCAGAGAGGAGGCGGCAGGAUGCUGUUUCCCCGAUUCCAUCCUCAGGGAGUGGAGACUGGAGGGGAGGUGCACUGACUCAGAUGAACUGUUCUCCCCCUUCUUUGAUAAGAAGUAGGUGGCAGCAGCCUCUGGAAAAGUCAGGGCCCUGGAGGUUACCUGGCCCAGGGCUACUACAGCCACAGGCCCCAGUGGCACCAUGCCACCCCUUCCAUGGCUCCACUCAAGGGGGCCACACAGCCACCGCCUCUUCCUCCUUUCCUUCAUCCCAAACUGGGACAAAAGACUUCAAGUUCUGGCUAAGAUGUAGCAGCAGCGGAUGCCCGGGCAUCCAAAGUGGAAAGCCAGGGCCCCGUGUCACCGGUGUGGGCAAACACACAUGCACGUGCACACAUGUUCUCCCUGAAUCACUCAGCAGCAGACAGGCUGCCGCCCUGGGGGUCUCAGCCCUGCUAGGGCUCACCAGGUGGAAGCCUAGGUGGUCUGACCUCAGUUUAGGAGUGGGUCAUUUACGUCAUCUUACCAUUUGGGGACGAGACAGGAAUGGUAUCCCUUAGGGACCCAGAGACACUGCAAACAGUGGGUGGCCAUGUAGGGCUGCAUGUCCCUGGGUCCAGGGGAAUGGAGGGAGCAAUAACUUGAAGAAGGGGGGAAGGGUUUCUUUUAUCCUUUUUUUUUUGUGUGACUUCUAUCAAAACA